AGAAUCCAAAGGCCGUAGGAGAAAGAAGGCUGGCGGUGUUUCCUCUUAGAGGGGAGAAACUCAGCCUGGGUAGGAGACCCAGCCCCACGCAGGGAAAACUGUGCUAACGCUUCCGAUGUGCGUGGCAGGUGCGGCGGCGGCGAAUACGGUUUGUCCUCGAGCCUAACCCUGUCUGUGUUGGUGUCAGCAGUGGCCCCCCUACCACACACACAGGGUCCCUGGCGUCCCAAGACCACUCCUGGCAGCCCCGCCACUGGCUGCGCCUGGAAGCCGCGUCCUCAGGCCUCGCCUGGCAUUUGCUGUCACAGAGGUUGCUUCCUUGGGUCCGUCCGUCCUCGCCCCUCCAGCCUGGGCGCCCCCCGACCCCUGUCUCAUUCCCUCCACCACAUGCAGCACAGUCCAGGAGGCUGGGGUCCAAGAGGGCCAUGGCUGGCACCCGGCUUAGUGCUGAGUCCCCAGUGCCCAGCAAGCCUGGCACCCAGGAGGUGGUCAGCAAACGCUUCUGAACGACAGGAAGUGGGACUCUUCAGCCAUCGAUGAUCCGCUGUGCGGCCACAGGCUCUGCUGUUCUCCUGCACUCAGGGUCCUCGGUACCCGCCGCUGCUGGCAGCUCCGUGGUGUCCGAGUCCGCGGUGAGCUGGGAGGCGGGCGCCCGGGCGGUGCUGCGCUGCCAGAGCCCGCGCAUGGUGUGGACCCAGGACCGGCUGCACGACCGCCAGCGCGUGCUCCACUGGGACCUGCGCGGCCCCGGGGGUGGCCCCGCGCGGCGCCUGCUGGACUUGUACUCGGCGGGCGAGCAGCGCGUGUACGAGGCGCGGGACCGCGGCCGCCUGGAGCUCUCGGCCUCGGCCUUCGACGACGGCAACUUCUCGCUGCUCAUCCGCGCGGUGGAGGAGACGGACGCGGGGCUGUACACCUGCAACCUGCACCAUCACUACUGCCACCUCUACGAGAGCCUGGCCGUCCGCCUGGAGGUCACCGACGGCCCCCCGGCCACCCCCGCCUACUGGGACGGCGAGAAGGAGGUGCUGGCGGUGGCGCGCGGCGCACCCGCGCUUCUGACCUGCGUGAACCGCGGGCACGUGUGGACCGACCGGCACGUGGAGGAGGCUCAACAGGUGGUGCACUGGGACCGGCAGCCGCCCGGGGUCCCGCACGACCGCGCGGACCGCCUGCUGGACCUCUACGCGUCGGGCGAGCGCCGCGCCUACGGGCCCCUUUUUCUGCGCGACCGCGUGGCUGUGGGCGCGGAUGCCUUUGAGCGCGGUGACUUCUCACUGCGUAUCGAGCCGCUGGAGGUCGCCGACGAGGGCACCUACUCCUGCCACCUGCACCACCAUUACUGUGGCCUGCACGAACGCCGCGUCUUCCACCUGACGGUCGCCGAACCCCACGCGGAGCCGCCCCCCCGGGGCUCUCCGGGCAACGGCUCCAGCCACAGCGGCGCCCCAGGCCCAGACCCCACACUGGCGCGCGGCCACAACGUCAUCAAUGUCAUCGUCCCCGAGAGCCGAGCCCACUUCUUCCAGCAGCUGGGCUACGUGCUGGCCACGCUGCUGCUCUUCAUCCUGCUACUGGUCACUGUCCUCCUGGCCGCCCGCAGGCGCCGCGGAGGCUACGAAUACUCGGACCAGAAGUCGGGAAAGUCAAAGGGGAAGGAUGUUAACUUGGCGGAGUUCGCUGUGGCUGCAGGGGACCAGAUGCUUUACAGGAGUGAGGACAUCCAGCUAGAUUACAAAAACAACAUCCUGAAGGAGAGGGCGGAGCUGGCCCACAGCCCCCUGCCUGCCAAGUACAUCGACCUAGACAAAGGGUUCCGGAAGGAGAACUGCAAAUAGGGAGGCCCUGGGCUCCUGGCUGGGCCAGCAGCUGCACCUCUCCUGUCUGUGCUCCUCGGGGCAUCUCCUGAUGCUCCGGGGCUCACCCCCCUUCCAGCGGCUGGUCCCGCUUUCCUGGAAUUUGGCCUGGGCGUAUGCAGAGGCCGCCUCCACACCCCUCUCCCAGGGGCUUGGUGGCAGCAUAGCCCCCACCCCUGCGGCCUUUGCUCACGGGUGGCCCUGCCCACCCCUGGCACAACCAAAAUCCCACUGAUGCCCAUCAUGCCCUCAGACCCUUCUGGGCUCUGCCCGCUGGGGGCCUGAAGACAUUCCUGGAGGACACUCCCAUCAGAACCUGGCAGCCCCAAAACUGGGGUCAGCCUCAGGGCAGGAGUCCCACUCCUCCAGGGCUCUGCUCGUCGGGGGCUGGGAGAUGUUCCUGGAGGAGGACACUCCCAUCAGAACUUGGCAGCCUUGAAGUUGGGGUCAGCCUCGGCAGGAGUCCCACUCCUCCUGGGGUGCUGCCUGCCACCGAGAGCUCCCCCACCUGUACCACCAUGUGGGACUCCAGGCACCAUCUGUUCUCCCCAGGGACCUGCUGACUUGAAUGCCAGCCCUUGCUCCUCUGUGUUGCUUUGGGCCACCUGGGGCUGCACCCCUUGCCCUUUCUCUGCCCCAUCCCUACCCUAGCCUUGCUCUCAGCCACCUUGAUAGUCACUGGGCUCCCUGUGACUUCUGACCCUGACACCCCUCCCUUGGACUCUGCCUGGGCUGGAGUCUAGGGCUGGGGCUACAUUUGGCUUCUGUACUGGCUGAGGACAGGGGAGGGAGUGAAGUUGGUUUGGGGUGGCCUGUGUUGCCACUCUCAGCACCCCACAUUUGCAUCUGCUGGUGGACCUGCCACCAUCACAAUAAAGUCCCCAUCUGAUUUUUA